AUGGGGACCUGGAUUUUAUUUGCCUGCCUCCUGGGAGCAGCUUUUGCCAUGCCUCUACCACCUCAUCCUGGGCACCCUGGUUAUAUCAACUUCAGCUAUGAGGUGCUUACCCCUUUGAAGUGGUACCAGAGCAUAAGGCCACCGUACCCUUCCUAUGGUUACGAGCCCAUGGGUGGAUGGCUGCACCACCAAAUCAUCCCCGUGCUGUCCCAACAGCACCCCCCGACUCACACCCUGCAGCCUCAUCACCACAUCCCAGUGGUGCCAGCUCAGCAGCCCGUGAUCCCCCAGCAACCAAUGAUGCCCGUUCCUGGCCAACACUCCAUGACUCCAAUCCAACACCACCAGCCAAACCUCCCUCCGCCCGCCCAGCAGCCCUACCAGCCCCAGCCUGUUCAGCCACAGCCUCACCAGCCCAUGCAGCCCCAGCCACCUGUGCACCCCAUGCAGCCCCUGCCGCCACAGCCACCUCUGCCUCCGAUGUUCCCCAUGCAGCCCCUGCCUCCCAUGCUUCCUGAUCUGACUCUGGAAGCUUGGCCAUCAACAGACAAGACCAAGCGGGAGGAAGUGAUGCUGCUCUGGGAUUAUUACCCCAUGGAAUCUUUCACGUCUUCCUGGCUUGGGUCCUACCUUGCUUCUAGCAGUAGGCACGAAACACAGAGCCUGAAAUACACACACCGUAUCUUCUUACCUCUCCAGGGUUCUUACACCUCAGCAAUAGCAGCAGCUCCAGGCAGUAGCGAGCCCCCAUACUCCCCACGCAGAGCCCCUGUGCAGUGUGGGAACAGAGAAGGAGACAGGAGGCAGGGAGGGACACUGCUCAAAGUGCUAGAGGAGCCGGCCAGGCAGUCUCCCUGUCUGGAAUGCACAACUAGAGGAUCUCGGAGGGAGAGAGCCUUGGGUCACUGUGAUCCUCUGAGUCAGACACCCUGGGGAGCUCUUAGUUCUGAAAGUCCUCCCCAGGCACAGAAGGCUGAAAGCCCCCAAGCACCCACUAGGAAGAAAAGUGUAAAAGUUAAAAAGUUAAAAAGUUGA